GCCUCGGCGGGGGCGGAGACGCCCCCACCUGCAAAGGCAGCCCCUGGGGCGUGCGAGGUUUCCUCCCCUGAGUCCCGGUUUUCCUUCUUGAGGACUUCUUGUCCCCUCUGACCCCAAGAUGCCUGGGGACUCAGUGGUCUUUGAGGAUGUGGCUGUGGACUUCACCCUGGAGGAGUGGGCUUUGCUGGAUUCUGCUCAGAGGGACCUCUACAGAGAUGUGAUGCUGGAGACCUUUCAGAACCUGGCCUCAGUAGAUGAUGAAACUCAAUUUAAGGCCAGUGGGUCAGUUUCUCAGCAGGAUAUUUAUGGAGAGAAAAUACCCAAGGAAUCUAAAAUAGCCACGUUCACCAGAAAUGUUUCCUGGGCCUCUGUUUUAGGAAAAAUUUGGGACAGUCUUAGCAUCGAAGAUCAAACCACAAACCAGGGGAGAAAUCUCAGUAGAAAUCAUGGGUUGGAGAGACUCUGUGAAAGUAAUGAUCAAUGUGGAGAAGCCCUCAGCCAGAUUCCACAUCUUAAUCUGUACAAGAAAAUUCCACCUGGAGUAAAACAGUAUGAAUACAACACGUACGGAAAAGUCUUCAUGCAUCGCCGCACAUCCCUCAAGAGUCCCAUCACAGUUCACACUGGACACAAACCAUAUCAGUGCCAGGAAUGUGGGCAGGCCUACAGUUGUCGUUCACACCUAAGAAUGCAUGUGAGAACCCACAAUGGAGAGAGACCCUAUGUGUGUAAAUUAUGUGGGAAAACCUUUCCUCGUACUUCCUCCCUCAAUCGGCAUGUAAGGAUUCACACUGCUGAGAAAACCUACGAAUGUAAGCAAUGUGGGAAAGCCUUUAUUGACUUCUCAAGUCUUACUAGUCAUCUCAGAAGUCACACCGGAGAGAAGCCAUAUAAGUGUAAGGAAUGUGGGAAAGCUUUCAGUUAUUCCUCAACGUUUCGAAGACACACAAUAACACACACUGGCGAGAAGCCAUAUAAAUGUAAGGAAUGUGCGGAAGCCUUUAGUUAUUCCUCAACUUUUCGAAGACAUAUGAUUUCACACACUGGAGAGAAGCCACAUAAAUGUAAAGAAUGUGGGGAGGCCUUCAGUUAUUCUUCGGCUUUUCGAAGACACAUGAUAACACACACUGGAGAGAAACCCUACGAAUGCAAACAAUGUGGGAAAACCUUCAUUUAUCUCCAGUCCUUUCGAAGACAUGAAAGGAUUCACACUGGAGAGAAACCCUACGAAUGCAAACAGUGUGGGAAGACCUUCAUUUAUCCCCAGUCCUUUCGAAGACAUGAAAGGACUCAUGGUGGAGAGAAACCCUAUGAAUGCAACCAGUGCGGGAAAGCAUUCAGUCACCCCUCCUCCUUUCGAGGACACAUGAGGGUGCACACUGGAGAGAAACCCUAUGAGUGCAAGCAAUGUGGGAAAACUUUCAAUUGGCCCAUAUCUUUACGAAAACAUAUGAGAACACAUACUAGAGAGAAACCCUAUGAAUGUAAGCAGUGUGGGAAAGCCUUCAGCUUGUCUGCUUGCUUUCGAGAACAUGUGAGAAUGCACCCUGAAGACAAAUCCUAUGAAUGCAAGCUAUGUGGGAAAGCUUUCUAUUGCCACAUAUCCUUACAAAAACAUAUGAGAAGACAUACCGCAGAGAAACUCUAUAAAUGCAAGCAGUGUGGGAAAGCUUUCAGUUGGCCUGAACUUUUGCAACAACAUGUGAGAACGCACACUGUAGAGAAGCCCUAUGAAUGUAAGGAAUGUGGGAAGGUCUUCAAAUGGCCAUCAUCUUUACCAAUACAUAUGAGACUGCACACUGGAGAGAAACCUUAUCAAUGUAAGCAUUGUGGGAAAGCAUUCAAUUGUUCCUCAUCCUUAAGGCGACAUGUGAGAAUACACACUACAGAAAAACAGUAUAAGUGUAAUGUAGGACAUCCUCCUGCAAAUGAAUUCAUGUGCAGUGCUUCAGAAAAGUCACACCAGGAGAGAGAUCUGAUCAAAGUUGUAAAUAUGGUGUUGCCUUUAUGAGUUCCUUAUCCUGAAAGUGGACACUCAAGGAGUGUGUCUGUAGUUCAUUUGCAAAUAAACAUUUAGUUGAAAAAUAAUUCUCCAAAUACUCUCAGCUAUCCUACAUGAAUUUGAACAGGUAGUUUCUUACGAUUCAGUAAAUAAAACUUUCAUCUUAGAGUGUUUUGGACUCAUGGAUGAUUUGAAGUGUAUUUUUAAUAUGCAAGUAGGUUCAAGUUUUAUUUAAUUUCUUAAAUUGUAACUGACUUAGUGUGACAGGUAUUGGAUAUUACGUAUCUAUUAUAUUUUCCACCUUUUUUACUGGGAGUAUUUUUAUUGUUUGGCCAGAGGAGCCUUAUUCCAUUUUUUAAGAAGUAGUUGGCAGAAUUUUGUAAUUAUGCAAAGUUGUUUAAGGAGUAUAGCCUCAAAUGAAUUGUAAUUUUUAAUGUUUGCCCAUUGCUGUUUGUCUUUGCUUGUGAUUGUGAAUUGGACAGUAGGCUUUGACUUGUGAUGUGACGGAGAAAUCCAGAGUUGCAGAUAGUUCUUCUGCAUUGUUGUCAGUGUGGGUAGUGUUAGGAACUUCAUUUGCUGGAAUGCAUUUCCUUUAUGGUUCCAUGUCCAAAUUUACCAAUAGCAAUAACUUGAAUGAAAUUUAGAAUGAAGAAGAAGUAAGUCAUCGCUGAGCUUUUGGGGUCACAUUAAAUGGAGAUGGACAGAUGCAUAGGGGCUUUGUGAACAUCAACCUUCAGCUUAUUUUCCAGAUUCUUAUUCCUGCCAAUCAAGAGUACCAUCAAAAGAAACACUUAAGUGCUUGAUUUCCACUGUGUCAGAGGUGUAGUCUUCCUCAGACAUCUCCAUUAACUUGAUAUUAGGGAUAUUCCUGUGUGGUCAGUCACCUAGAGUCUGGAUUUUUCUCAAAACCCUGCAUGACCUCUUGACCACUGAUUCAGACUGUCUUGUUUGGCAGUCUCUGAGCUUCUGAUUCUCCCGUUCUGUAGAUCUUAACAUAUUUGCAUGGGGUCUAAUUUAUAUAGUGAACACCUUGUUAUCUUAAUACUUCCAGUGGCUCUGUGAUCCUGAUUCCACCACGAAAGCCACAGUGUUGCAGUCAAAGAAGAAAAACAACACAUGGGACUUUGUACCCUAUUGCAUUUUUAAGUGUGCCUGCCGAGUCCUAUGUGAGAACAAAUACCUUCCUCAUAUAUUAGAUUUAGGGAGAUUUCUGUUACUCAGAACUAAAUGCAGUUUCUUGAUAUAGGUUAAAUUAUUAGGUUUGAUUAUGUAUCAUUAAAAAUAAUGUGGAUUUUGUUUCAAGGAAAACCUUCUGUAGAUAUUUCUUAGAAAUAUCCUGUUUAGCUGGGCACAGUAGCUCAUGCCUGUAAUCCCUGCACUUUGGGAGGCUUGAGGUCAGGAGUUUGAGACCAGCCUGGUUAACAUGGUGAAACCCUGUCUCUACUAAAAACACAAAAAUUAGCCAGGCAUGGUGGUGAGUACCUGUAACCCCAGCUACUUGGGAGGCUGAGACAGGAGAAGUGCUUGAACCUAGGAGGCGGAGGUUGCAGUGAGCCAAGAUCACACCACUGCACUCCAGCCUGGGAGACGGGGAAAGACUCCAUCACACAAGCAAGAAAAGAAAAAAAAAUCCUAUUUACUGUGCUUUCAAAUUAGUUGUUUAGAGACUAUAUUAAUUUCCCAGGGCUGCCAUAACAAAGUACAAAAACUGGGUGACAUAGGAAAACAAACUUUUUGUUUCUCAGUUCUGGACCCAGAAAUCCAGAAACAAGGCAUUGGCAGGACCAUGCUUUUUCUGAAGAUGCUAGGGAAGGAUCUGUUUCAGAACUCACCUAGCUUCUGGUAGUUCCUUAGCUUGUGGCAGCAUAACUCUAAUUUUCACAUGGCAUUCUCCCUGUGUGUGUGUCUCUCCAUGUGACAAUAUUUUUAUACAUACACACCACUCAUUGGGUUAGGCCCCACUCUACUUCAGUAUGAUUUUACCUUAACUAAUUACAUUGGCAACAGCUCUCUUUUCGCAUACUGAGGCACCGCGAAUUAAGAUUUCAACGUAAAAAUUUUAGGAGACCCAAUUCAACCCAUAACACUAAGAAAUGUUAUUUUUUGUUUACCGAGAGAAUUACAGAUUUCAAAUCAACUUUGUAAUUUUGAUAAUUUAAGCAUGUUACAUUUUGAAUCAGUAUUACCAAGUAUAUACAAAUACAGGUAUUUUUUCAUAUAAAUGUUAUUUUUAAUUGCUGUAUACUUAACAUUUGCCAUUAAAAUGAUUUUUUUUUUUUGAGACAGAGUCUCGCUCUGUCACCCAGGCUGGAGUGCAGUGGCACGACCUUAGCUCACUGCAACCUUCAUCUCCCAGGUUCAGUUGAUUCUCCUGCCUCAGCCUCCCGAGUAGUUGGGAUUACAGGCAUGCACCACCACACCCAGCUAAUUUUUUUAUUUUUGGUAGAGAUGGGGUUUCACCAUGUUGGCCAGGCUGGUCUUGAACUCCUGACCUCAGGUGAUCUGCCCACCUUGGCCUCCCAAAGUGUUGGGAUUACAGGCAUGAGCCACCACACCCGGCCUAAAAUGAUUUCUUAUUUGUGGUUAAUAACAAUUAAAAAGCGGAAAUAAUGGUUUUGUCAAGGCCCUCUACCCAGAAACCACCAGGAUCACACUGGUAGUCAAAGAAAAUUUGCUGUGUUGAGUUGAAGUUUGAACACAUGAUCAAGAAAGGGCUGUGGCUUGUAUCAGAGGGUGUUUAAAAGGAUUUACUAUCAGAUUUGGCCUUGUGUUCUGUGAUUUUGGUGAGCGUUCAAGGAAGCCAGGCUUUGGUCUGGAUUGGAUGUUCUCAGGUCAUGAAUAUAAUUCUCUGGGAACUCCCAAAGUUCUCAUCUACAAAGCAGAAGUUAAUUGGAGCUGAAAACUAAUCAGUAAAGCCACAGCAGCCAGUCAUAUGGGGGAGAAGAGGGGAAUGUUUGAUGGUUUUUGUGGUUUAGAGGUGAGUUCCGGAAAAAAAGAAGACAUGUUUGACAUCCUCAAACGAGAAAAUUUUUCAUGUGUUUUAUAGGCCAAGGAGGCAGAAGCUUUUGUUUUAAUGAGCCAGAAAGCCCCAAAAGCCUAUUUAAGUUUUCUCAGGUAUCAUUUCAACCUCUGAACUUCCAGAAUUAACUAGGGAAGAGGAAAAACAUGUAACACCUUAGAGUUUUAUUAAAGAGCAAACAAUAUCCAGUAAUCUCCAUUACUUUCCAUGUUAACAUAAGUUUUCAUAACGCUCUAUAGAUGAAUGUGAUUUGGCAGUCACUUGUAUUUCUUAACACCCACUUACCCAUCAUUCCCUCUUAGAUGAAAAAAGUUAAGCACGGGGACAACAGAGUCUUGUAUAUUCAUGUAGCUCAUGAUGAUGGAAUCAAGUUUGAAGGCUUAACCUGUGCUUAACCUAUAUUGGGCAUUGUCAAGACUUAAAUUUAGAACACUGGAAAGCAAGUAUAAUUAAUUUUACAAAUAGGGCAUCAAAUUUUACAAAGACUCCUAAGGCUAUAUGGUAUUCCUUUUAUAAGACAUGGAAAAGGCAAAGAUAAGGGAAACGAACAAAUCGCUGGUUAGAAGUAGGGGAUUUGAGUACAUAUGGGCUUAAGAGUGUUCUGUCAUGAUUGUAGUGGUGAAAACAAGCAUUUGCAAAAACUCAUAAGGCUACUCUUAAAAUAGCAAAUUUUGUUGUAUGUAUAUUUUAAAGUUAAACAAUAAAAAUGCUUUCAGUUUAUUAAAGAACUCAAGACCAGGUGCAGUGGCUCAUGCCUAUAAUCCCAGCACUUUGGGAAGCUGAGGCGGGAGGAUUGCUUGUGGCCAGGAGGUUGAGGCUGCAGUGAACUAUGAUCAUGCACUGCACUCUACACUGGGCGACAGAGCAAGACCCUGUCUCAAAAAAAAAGGAAUACAAAACAUUCCUGAAACUUGACAUGUAAGUUCGCAAUAAGACUUUUCCCUAGCUGGGCGCGGUGACUCAUGCCUGUAAUCUCAACAUUUUGGGAGACUGAGGCAAGAGGAUCACUUGAAGUCAGGAGCUAGACACCAGUCUGGGCAACAUAGCGAGACCUCAACUCUACCAAAAAAUUAAAAAGUGAGCCAGGCGGGGUGGUGCACGUCUGUGGUCCCAGCUACUUGGCAGGCUGAAGCAGGAGGAUCACUUGAGGCCUUGAGGAGCCAUGAUCGUGCCACUGCACUCCAGCUUGGGUGACAGAGCAAGACUGUCUCAAAAAAUAAAAAUAAAAAAACAAGACUUCCCCCACCAUCUUGGAAUUCUCUGGAGGAAAUGUAGGGCUGGUUGACAAGGACUUGUGCCUCGUCAGACCCUGUUUGAAACCCAGUCUGAAGUUUUGAAACACCCACAAGGGCCAUACCUGACUUUAUCUCACGCACAUAACAGGAGAGAAGAAGGAGGUCUUCCAGAAUCUGUCUUUGAGUUUACACCAGGUUCUUCCCAUCUGAUCUUUGGGAAUGCUGUGGUUCUGAAACAUAAAACGGGGACCCUACACUUCUUCCCAGGAAUAUCCUGCCUGGGAGCAUCCUGAUCCUGUCUUCAGACAAGGGGCAUCCGCAUCUUGUUUUCUAGGGCCUUUCCUGAGGCCACUUCCAGCUCCAAAGUUCUCAUCUCAAGCUCAGCUCUGUGUCUUCAUGCUGGGAAACGUCUUUAUGGAUCCCCAAACUCCUCUUGCUGUUGGGAACACGUGGCAGCCCUGCGUUGUGAGGUGAGAGAAGAGGCAGUGGCAGAACCCAUGCCAUGGAGACACGCCCAUCAGCCACAGCAGCUCCUGCUACUGCAUAAAUCCAUAGGCACAAUCACACGCCUCACGGUGUCAACAUCUCCCAUGACAUCACAAAGAUGCCCAGCUGGGACCCACCUACAGUGAUGGGGUGAUGGGGUUUCACCUAUAAGCGGGCAAACAGGCACUCCUCCUCACUGUCCAGUCACCUGACGUGCUUUUUCUGCGCACUCAGGUCGUGACACCCCAGGAGGUGCCUAUCGCGCCCCAAGCUCCUCACGUGCCUCCUCCCCACAGUCCAGGACGCGUCUUACUAACGCCUCACCAGAGCGCAUGCGCCCUCCUCAGGAGCAGCCUCAAAGCGCGCAGCCUCAGCCCAUUGGCCUGCGGGAAGUGGAGUUCCCGAACAGAAGCCCCUCAGUCUCCGGAAGCCCCGCCCGGCAGACUGUUCCCAGGAUGCAACACGGGCUCGCGUCUAAAAGAGCUGUGCUUUGUUGGGGCUAUCUGGGAGUUUCCGCCUUCCAUGAAGUGCGCAGGCGCACUUAGGCGAGGCGGGGCGACUCUAGGAAGUGGAGACAUCAAGAGUGGUACUGGAAGUGGCGGAAGCUCUCCUCUUGCCCUCUUCAGCUUCCGGUGUGGUGGGUCCCGGAUAUCGCGUGGCUGUGGCAGGUAGACAGCCCGUGCUCCAGAGGCCUUCAUCUUGUGAUGGCAGAUGUACUUGAGUAGACACGACAGACGGGGAAGGACCCUGAUGGUCCGAGGGACCUUCCACAGCAAGUAGAAGGCACUGCUGUGAAUAUGAUGGCGUCAGAGGUGACUGCAAAAAAGGACAGGGCAGCUGGGCGAGGAAGAGAUACCAGUGAUGUCCUAACUGAGCUCCCUGGGUCUGGUAGUGAGGAGCUCAGUCUUAGAAUAUGAGCCGUGUCAGGGGCUACAGCAUCAUCACUCUUGUCCUGUCGCAGACUCAGGCUCCCUGUUCUCAGGUUCUUAUGUAGACAGUGAGGGCUCAGGGAGGCUCCCACCACCACCACCACCAGCACCACCACUCCAUCAAAACGGCUGAAGGACCUUCCUUUAGGGUUCGGGGGAUCUCCUCCUUCCACAAGGGAUGGAUGUGAAGACAACUCAUUCUUUGAUGUUCAGAUGGUUGUGGCCCUCUGAUGAGAUGUGUGCACACCUUGCCAAAUGCAUAUGUCUGUUGAGCCUGGACAUUAAGUAUUUCUUGAUGUUCUUCUGUGUAACAGGUGAUGUCCUAGGUGCUGCAGUGAACAGAAGAGACAAAAUAUCCUUGUUCCCUUGAAGCUAAUGUCGUAGGGGCCCAAAACAAAGCAAACAAACAAAAAAAAGGAAUGCAAGUCAAGUACACUUUGUAUGGACAGUGGUAAUUCCUAAGAAGGAAAACAAAGAUGGACUUAAGGGGUGCAGAGGGCCUGGACUAUGUGUGUCUGUGGGAUAGUCUGUUACUACCUCUGGGACUCUCAUCUCUUGAGUGUGCUUGGGUGUGUCCAACCGUUUUUCCUAGUGACAAAGUCUGGGUAAUUCUGUGGGGACAUAUAUUGGUGUAUCUGGGAGGUCCCAUGUGUCUCAGUGGUGGUCCCUGUUUUCAGGAAAGAGUGUCUGUGAAUGUCCAUGUGUCUCACUGCACAGCUGUGAUUUUUCUGUGUCUCUGUGUUUUCCAGUCUUUGUGUGAUGAAAUAUAAAGGCCUAGCAGGCUCAGAGUUAUUAAUGAAUUGUACUUAAGCGUUGAGAGGCAUAUAUUUAUUGCACUAUUAAAUUCUUCCAAAAUAUA